AACUGCGACCGGGGUUCAGCGCUCGGGUGAGGAGCUGGUGGCGUCGGCAGGUUCGAGGCGAUUCGAGGUGAGGGGGUCAAGCGGAGAGGCUCGGAGUCGGAGAAAGCUGUCGCGACCCAGCCACCCAGGGUCUGGGGUCGGUGGGAGCUCCAGCUAGGAUGAUCGAGGUUGUUUGCAACGACCGUCUGGGGAAGAAGGUCCGCGUUAAAUGCAACACGGAUGAUACCAUCGGGGACCUUAAGAAGCUGAUUGCAGCCCAAACUGGUACCCGUUGGAACAAGAUUGUCCUGAAGAAGUGGUACACGAUUUUUAAGGACCACGUGUCUCUGGGGGACUAUGAAAUCCACGAUGGGAUGAACCUGGAGCUUUAUUAUCAAUAGAUGAGAAUCCUCAUCUUCCUGCCCCGCUUUCCUCUCCCAUCCUCAUCCCCCACACUGGGAUAGAUGCUUGUUUGUAAAAACUCACCUUAAUAAAGACUUAGAUGUUG